AGUCCCGUCACAGCGUCGGCGCCGGCCGGGGCCGAACCCGGAAGUGGCCGAGCCCGCGCGCCCGCCGGUCCCGUCGCCGCCGCCCCGCACUCGGGCGAGCGCGGGAGCCGCGCAGUAGACGGAGCGCGCCCGGCCGAGCGGGCCAUGGCCGCGGGGGCCGCCGCCGCAGGUGGUGGCGCGCGGUGAGGAGAGCGCGGCGCCCCCUCCGGGGCGGAUGGAACGCGGCUCGGCGGGCGGGCAGUGCCGGCGUCCGCGGCUGGAAUGGUGCUGGCUGUGUUGGUCGGUGCCUGCGUUCUGAAGCCCGAGAGGAGCCACAAUGGAGACGCCGCCGCUGCCUCCCGCAUCUCGUUGGCUGUAUCUUCAAAAUGUCCAGAACCCAGCCAGUUUUCAUCACCUCCACUGCGACUGUCCUCCCUAAGCCACUGUCAUUUUUUAGUGAAUUAUUGUAAUAUCCUGCUAAAUAGUUGCCCCCUUUUCAUCUUUGACCCGUGUAGAGUGUUCUCAACCAGCAGCCAAAGUGGUCUUUGGAAAACAUGCACAAAGCAGGGUCAUCAGAAGCCUCUCGAUUCAAAAGAUGAUAAUACCGAAAAACACUGCCCAGUGACAGUGAAUCCUUGGCAUAUGAAGAAAGCUUUCAAAGUCAUGAACGAAUUAAGAAGUCAAAAUUUGCUGUGCGAUGUCACAAUUGUGGCAGAAGACAUGGAAAUUUCUGCUCAUAGAGUGGUGCUGGCCGCCUGUAGUCCUUAUUUUCAUGCCAUGUUUACAGGUGAGAUGAGUGAGAGCCGAGCAAAGAGAGUUAGAAUAAAAGAGGUAGAUGGCUGGACCCUGAGGAUGCUAAUUGAUUAUGUUUACACUGCAGAAAUUCAGGUUACAGAAGAAAAUGUACAGGUACUUCUCCCAGCAGCUGGUCUCUUACAGUUACAGGAUGUGAAGAAGACUUGUUGUGAAUUUUUGGAAUCCCAGCUUCACCCUGUCAACUGCUUAGGAAUCCGGGCUUUUGCUGAUAUGCAUGCAUGUACCGACCUUCUGAACAAGGCCAACACCUAUGCAGAGCAACAUUUUGCAGAUGUUGUACUUAGUGAAGAAUUUCUCAAUCUUGGCAUCGAACAAGUGUGCAGCUUAAUCUCAAGUGACAAACUUACCAUUUCUUCAGAAGAGAAGGUAUUUGAAGCAGUAAUAGCAUGGGUGAACCAUGACAAGGAUGUGAGGCAAGAGUUUAUGGCCCGACUGAUGGAACAUGUACGGUUACCUUUGCUUCCUCGGGAAUAUUUAGUUCAGAGGGUUGAAGAGGAAGCAUUGGUCAAGAAUAGCAGUGCUUGCAAAGAUUACCUCAUUGAAGCAAUGAAGUACCAUUUGCUGCCAACAGAGCAGCGUAUAUUAAUGAAGAGUGUCCGGACCCGGCUGAGGACACCCAUGAACCUUCCCAAAUUGAUGGUGGUGGUUGGGGGCCAAGCACCAAAGGCUAUCCGGAGUGUGGAAUGCUAUGACUUUAAAGAAGAAAGGUGGCACCAAGUAGCAGAGUUGCCUUCCAGGAGGUGCAGGGCAGGCAUGGUCUACAUGGCUGGACUUGUUUUUGCUGUUGGUGGCUUUAAUGGCUCAUUAAGAGUUCGCACUGUAGAUUCCUACGACCCUGUGAAGGACCAGUGGACCAGCGUUGCUAACAUGAGAGACCGGAGAAGCACUUUGGGAGCUGCUGUGUUAAAUGGAUUAUUAUACGCUGUGGGAGGCUUUGAUGGGAGUACAGGUUUGUCAUCUGUGGAAGCAUACAACAUAAAGUCUAAUGAGUGGUUUCAUGUAGCUCCCAUGAAUACAAGGAGGAGCAGUGUUGGUGUGGGUGUUGUUGGAGGUUUGCUCUAUGCUGUAGGAGGUUAUGAUGGAGCAUCACGUCAGUGUCUUAGCACAGUAGAAUGCUAUAAUGCUACAACAAAUGAGUGGACCUAUAUAGCAGAAAUGAGCACCAGGCGGAGUGGAGCAGGUGUUGGUGUGUUAAACAAUUUAUUGUAUGCUGUAGGAGGUCAUGAUGGCCCUUUAGUACGAAAAAGUGUUGAAGUAUAUGAUCCCACCACUAACGCAUGGAGACAGGUUGCAGAUAUGAACAUGUGCAGAAGAAAUGCAGGAGUUUGUGCAGUUAAUGGUCUGUUAUAUGUUGUUGGAGGGGAUGAUGGUUCCUGUAACUUGGCGUCAGUAGAAUAUUAUAACCCAACAACCGAUAAAUGGACAGUUGUGUCAUCGUGUAUGAGCACAGGGAGAAGUUAUGCAGGGGUCACAGUUAUUGAUAAACCAUUAUGAGCCUGAAGGACAUUUUCAGCAUAUUUAUACAUGAGAAACAGCCUUCAACAAGUAUUUGUGAAGUGACUGAGAAUCUAGCACUUCUCCACUUGUAGCUGCACUUUAAGUCUCAGCAGAAGAUACGAUCGUCUGCCUUUAUAGGCCUCAGAUACUGAAGAUUAUUUUUGGUAGAAGCACCGUGUAGGCUUUUUCUGCAAUGAGCAGCAGCUGACUGAAUUUUCAUAAGAAACUUGGACUGCAGGACUUAAUCUGUAGUCUUUAGACAACAGUUGCUUUCAUAAAGACUAGUUCUUAUCAACCUUGAAUGACUACAGAUUAUUUUGUGAAGGAGGAUGAAGUAAUGUGUGUUCUUGUAAAAUUAAAUUUUAUCUUUAUUUCUUCUAAAAAUCUGUAUACCAGGAACUGAAAAUCUUUGAACAGAUAUUAAAAUCUACGUAAGUAUACAAACUAGUUGAGGGAUACACUGUUUGCUUUUAUAAAAUAACUUUGAUUACAUGAAUAUAAUAAAUUAUGUGCAUAUAAAUGUGUGUCUAUAUGCUUUCCUUUAAAUAUGUUUGAAAAGAUGUUUGAAACUUGAUUAUACUAUUUAUAAUUGGCACAGUACUUUGAAUUAUGCCAGUACUACAUUGUAAAACAGAGUUGUAUUUUUUGAUAUUUAACAAUGCUUAACACUUUAAAUGCCACUUCUGAGGAAUGGACCUGGUGUAACACACUUGAAUAUGUGUGAUGCCAAACUUUUUAAAAUACAAUAUAAAUUAUGCUUAUUUAUUAUUUUCUUUAGUUUAAUCUUGGUCAUGUUUUGGUGUGUAUUUUUAAUUUUUUUCUUAAAUUAACACUUUGGCAUGAACAUUACUGCAGGUUUUUGAUGAAUAUAAUGAAUGUAUGGAAUUCAAUUGAAUUUGCAUGGUCUUCGGAAUUUUUUCUGUGUGUAUAAAUUUAGCUGCUAUUAACAGAAGAGAGAACUUUCUGUGAGUAGCCAUGUGUGUUGAUCAGAUACAGUUUUUCUGAGAUCUUCAAUUAAUCUCACUUUAAAAAUGACCAAAACAUGUCUUUCUUGAAUUAACUUUGAAUAAAAGUUUGUAUAUUAUUUGUUUCA